UGAGCCACCAGCCACAGCCUGGGCCAGUGAAGACCUUUGAUAAAUCCAUCUAUUCUACAGGGUUCUUGGAGAUGAGAUUGCCUGUUGAGUAUAUUGGGGGCUCUUCAAGAGACUAAAUCUCAAAGAAAGAGCUUCUUGAGGAACUGAGGAGUACCAUGUAGAAAUGAGAAAGAAGGUGAGGAGAAGUUUGAAAAAUUCUGCACUCAAAUAAAAGAGAAAAACAGGAGGACAAAGGACAGAGUUGGGUACUAGAGACUAUGAUAAAUCUCUAAGAUUCUUAGGUCUUCUUGGUUACUGUCAUUCCCAUAUCCAUUACUCUUAGAUGAAAGUGGUCCUUGUGUUUAUCUUGACAAAUAGCAAAUAAGUGGGACCAUGCAAACAAGCAUUGGUCUCUUUUAUUCAUUCAUGCAAUAAGUAUUAAUUAGCAGUAACUAUAUUCCAAGCACUGUGCUCAAUGCUAGGAGUGCAGGAUGAGGAAAAUUUAGUCUGCUCAGGGAGCUCACAAUUCCAGGGUGGAGGGGGUGGAGACUAAGAGGUGAUAGAUUGCUAAGGUAGAGAGGGGCACAGCAGCUGGGAUAGCACAGACUGGCAGUCCAUAAUCCUGUUUAGAGAGUCACGGAAGACUUCCUGGAGGACUCUGCAGGAUUAGAAAUGGGUAAAUCAAAUAUGGUUUUGUCAUUCAAAAUUGUGGCACAUCUCUCCAGUUAUUUAGAUCUUCUUUUACGUCCUUUUAGAGGAUUUUUAUACAUUUUUCUACAAAGAUCUUAUACAGUGUUUGUGAGCUUAAUUUCUAAGUAAUUCAUAAUGUUUGGUGCUAUUGUGAAGAGUAUGUUAUUUUGCAUUCUUUUUGUGGUUGGUUAUUGUUGGUUAUAGAGACGUACAAUUUAUGGUAUCUUGUAACUUGCAAUCUUUUGGUACUCUCUAAUUCUCAGAGUUGUUGGAUUUUAUUCGGUUUUCUAAGUAAGAAAAACAACAUCUGCAAACAAUGGCAACCUUUUCUCAUGUUUUCCAGCACUAAUACUUCUUAUUUCCUUCCUGUGUGUUAUUGCACUUAUAUCUUAUUGAACAACAUGGUGACUGUGGGCAUCUUUGUCUUCUUCCAGACCCUCAGUGGAAUGUGUAUUAAAUUUUCUCUUUUGAGAGUGGUGGUUUCUGUGGAGGUAGGUUCUGGUAGAAACCAUUUUCAGAUUCAUAAUGUGCCCUUCUGUGUCUAAGUUUUUCUAAGAAUUUUUACACUAAAUAUGCAUUGAACUUUAACAGAUUUUUAAAGCAUCAAAAGAUGCUUUAUUUAAAUUGCAUCUUUUGAGAUUCCCAUAUGAUUUUUCUUCUGUAGUACCAAUGAUGGAAUGAAUUACAUUUAGAGAUUUUAUCCGAUUUUGUACUAUCCUUACCUUCUGUGAUAAAAAUCAUCUGAUUAUAACGCAUUACCACAUUAACAUACCACUGGAUUUCAUUAUCUAGUGUUUUACUCAAGAUCAUGACAUUUCAAAAUAGGUAGCAUUGACGUGUUAUUUUCUCUGCUUUCACUGUUCUUAUCUAGCUCUGGAAUCAAGGACAUACUAUGUCAUUAAAUGAGAUGGGCAGCUUUCCUUCUUUUUCUGUACUCAGAAACAACUUGUAAAGUGGGAAUUAUCUGCUCCUUGAAUGUUUGAUAGAACUUACCCAUAAAACUGUCUACGUCUAAUAUUUGAGGAAGGGAGGUAGGACAUAGGAAGAUUCUCUGUUAUAUGAAUUUAGUCCAUGGAGAUUUGUCUGUAUACAUUUUCUGUUUCUUUUGUGUUGGUUUUGACACUCUUUUUUUUUAGGUGUUCAUGGAAGAAAAGGAACAUGUCCUGAGGUUACAGAAAGGGAAAGGAGAGCUAUCCCAUUGCUGGGCAGAGGACUGUCAGAAUAGAUGUCUGUGUGAAGGGGAGUUAAAUGUUCCUUCUCUGAUCAGUGUGUUCUAUUCAUCCAUCCUAAGGAGGGAACCUCAAGAGGAAGAUGUUCAGCUCAUAUGGAGCAUUGGCUGUGAUGACUACUUAGGCUCCGACAAAGUCGUGGACAAAUGUGGGGUGUGUGGAGGAGACAACACGGGCUGUCAGGUUGUGUCGGGCGUGUUUAAGCAUGCCCUCACCAGCCUGGGCUACCACCGCGUCGUGGAGAUUCCCGAGGGAGCCACGAAAAUCAACAUCACGGAGAUGUACAAGAGCAACAACUAUUUGGCCCUGAGAAGUCGUUCUGGACGCUCCAUCAUCAAUGGGAACUGGGCAAUUGAUCGACCAGGAAAAUACGAGGGCGGAGGGACCAUGUUCACCUACAAGCGUCCAAAUGAGAUUUCGAGCACUGCCGGAGAGUCCUUUUUGGCGGAAGGUCCCACCAACGAGAUCUUGGAUGUCUACAUGAUACACCAGCAGCCAAACCCAGGCGUGCACUACGAGUACGUGAUCAUGGGGACCAACGCCAUCAGCCCCCAGGUGCCACCCCACAGGAGACCAGGGGAACCCUUCAAUGGCCAGAUGGUGACAGAAGGCAGGAGCCAGGAGGAGGGAGAACAGAAAGGGAGGAACGAGGAGAAGGAAGACUUGCGUGGGGAGGCCCCUGAGAUGUUCACCUCAGAAUCGGCACAGACCUUCCCAGUCAGGCAUCCAGACAGAUUUUCUCCCCAUCGACCGGACAACUUGGUGCCACCAGCACCGCAGCCCCCACGGCGCAGCCGGGAUCACAACUGGAAGCAGCUUGGGACAACAGAAUGUUCCACGACCUGUGGGAAAGGAUCGCAGUACCCUAUUUUCCGCUGUGUGCACAGAAGCACUCAUGAAGAGGCUCCUGAGAGUUACUGUGACUCCAGCAUGAAGCCGACCCCCGAGGAGGAGCCCUGCAACAUCUUCCCUUGCCCAGCCUUCUGGGACAUCGGGGAGUGGUCUGAGUGCAGCAAGACCUGUGGCCUGGGCAUGCAGCACCGCCAGGUUCUGUGCCGCCAGGUGUACGCCAACCGCAGCCUGACGGUGCAGCCCUACCGCUGCCAGCACCUGGAGAAACCUGAGACCACCAGCACCUGCCAACUCAAGAUCUGCAGCGAGUGGCAGAUCCGGACCGACUGGACCUCGUGCUCGGUGCCCUGCGGCGUGGGACAGAGGACCCGUGAUGUGAAGUGUGUGAGCAACAUUGGGGAUGUGGUUGACGAUGAGGAAUGCAACAUGAAGCUCCGGCCGAAUGACAUUGAGAACUGCGACAUGGGACCCUGUGCCAAGAGCUGGUUCCUCACCGAGUGGAGCGAAAGGUGCUCAGCGGAGUGUGGGGCCGGAGUGCGGACACGCUCGGUGGUGUGCAUGACCAACCAUGUCAGCAGCCUGCCCCUGGAGGGCUGUGGGAACAACCGGCCGGCAGAGGCCACCCCAUGUGACAACGGACCCUGCACGGGCAAGGUGGAGUGGUUUGCCGGGAGCUGGAGUCAGUGUUCCAUCGAGUGUGGGAGCGGGACGCAACAGAGGGAGGUGAUUUGUGUUAGAAAGAAUGCAGACACCUUUGAAGUGUUGGACCCCUCUGAAUGUUCUUUCCUGGAGAAACCCCCCAGCCAGCAAUCCUGCCACCUCAAGCCUUGCGGAGCCAAAUGGUUUAGCACCGAAUGGAGCAUGUGUUCCAAGAGCUGCCAGGGUGGCUUUCGGGUCCGGGAAGUGCGGUGUCUGUCUGAUGACAUGACUCUAAGUAACCUCUGUGACCCUCAGUUGAAACCAGAAGAGAGAGAAUCUUGUAACCCUCAGGACUGUGUCCCUGAAGUUGAUGAAAACUGCAAGGACAAGUACUACAACUGCAACGUGGUGGUCCAGGCAAGACUCUGUGUCUACAACUACUACAAGACCGCCUGCUGUGCCUCCUGCACCCGUGUGGCCAACAGGCAGACGGGCUUCCUGGGGAGCAGAUAACACUCCUGCACCCCCAUCAGUAGGGCAGCAUCACUGCCUUCCCGGGGGCUUCAGCAGUGCGCCUGGCUGGCUGCUGCUCCACCACGGGCCCCCUGGCCCAGGCGCUGCCAACCAACUUAGUCACCACCCCUGCCUCCGGUGAAUGCACCCCGUGGUACCCAGGGGCUUUUUACACAAGAUGUUUGAAAGCCACAGUCAGUCCUUUAAGCAUCACCAUGUACUGAUGAUCCCCUCCUUGGACCUGGCAUCUGCUAAUGGUGCCCUUUGAAAGUCAAGCAGUGGGAAGUACAUGGAGCUCUCAGCCCUGCUCCCAUCUGGCACCUUCAAGUCAGCAGAUGGGCCACUGACUGAGCACUGCCCCGUCCCUGGUGCUACUGGUCUUUCUAAACUUAGCACCCUGGAGAGUCCAAGGAGGCAGCGCCCCCAACCCAGCGCCCCACUAAGCCUUGCUGACACGCGUGCAUCCCUCUGUGACCUCAGCCCAGAUGUGCCUGUUUUCAUUCUCAAAGACAUUAGACUGUUUUCCUGCCCUAUGACACAGAUAGCUCACAUGAAUAUUGUGCUUUAUUUAGCAGGUGUACUCACAGAUACUAGCUCCUUAGCAGCUCACAACAUCCCAGAAUGGGAGGCAGGGGGUGACUCAUUAUCCCCAUUUUACUGACAGGGAAACUGAGGCUCAACUUAAGUAAUUGACCUGCCAGGUAUAUUCACCCAUCCAGUGGAAGAGCUGAGUCCCCGCCCCAGUCAUCUACCAGUAUCCAGCCUGGGGCCUGUACUUAGAUGUGAAAGGUGCUGCUUCAUUUCUGACCAAGAGACUGAGAAGUUUCCCAGAAUGCAAACAAAGCCCAGGCCCCUGAAAUCUUUCCGGUCAAGCCUUUAUCCCAGCACUCAGUUGUUUUGGAUGUCUGUUCCUACUUGCCCUUACCCCCAAAGUUACAGAUCCUAGUUACAGGACUCUGCCAGCUUUGUUAAACUGUCCGUGAGACAAGAAAGCCAUUGGGGAAACCAGGUGAUUGCCUGAAAUUCUUACUCCGUUCCAAGUGCUGUUCCUCCCAGGAAAUCAAAGGCCAGGGUCCUUAUGGCCGUGGAGCCUUCCCGACCACAGAGCCAACUUGUGAAGCACACAGCUCUGCAGCCUGGGCUCUGCCCUGCCUCAGCCGCCUCCCCCACGCUCUUCACCACGUUCCUGGAGAGUCCGGCCAACCUGUCCCAGCCGAAACACUGCUGUAUUAGAAAAAGUCUCUUUCUGGUCUUUCUGGUUUUGUUUAUGAAUUUCCCUCUGUGGCCACAAAUUCCUCCCCUCCCCCAUGACUCACAGUCCAUAUGGCCCACCCCCAGACUUGAGCACCAAGCUCUGCAUUAAUGCAGUUGGCCUGCGACAAGGAGCUGUGGACCCUUCCCCAUCUCUUCCAAUUCACUUUCCCCAACUAUCCAGUUCCAGAGGCCGCAGGCCUGGAAGGAUGCAGUGCAUAUUGAAAGGUGGACCCUCUGAAAACAGUUAAGAGGAAUAUAUGUAUGUUUUACCCAUUAAGAAAAAAUGGCAAGCUAAACAAAUGUUAAACUUACAGAAAAUUUGUCUUAUGGUCCUGAGCAUAUUUCCCUUUUAGAGCAAGCCUGGAUUCUUAGCAAAGUGUUUCCCCCAUUUGCUCUUUUAGCUGACAAAUCUGCCACUGUGAUGAUGGUUUGCAGCUUUUGGAAGCAGUAUGGCAACCUGGCCUGACAUGCUCUUUAGGCUUCCACUAACCUGGGGCUUUCAGAAAUUCUAUUUGGCCUUUCUGUGGGUAGCUUUCCAGCUUCUCUUCUAGGGAGCCCCAGGCAUCAUUUCCCAAAAGCAUCCCCAUCUCCUGAUUCUCUUGGAACUCCUACAGAUAAGCAUCCUGGCAGAGGCCCAGGCUCCCAAACCGACAAAGUGAAAAGAGACCAGAGAGGCCAAGCAUAUUGACUGGUGCUGUUCAGGGCCUGCUCUUUUCCACUCACCACUUGUUUUGCUGCUUGUCACGAGGAGAGUUGUUCCUGUAUGUGGCUGCUCUCAGAUCUUUCCAAGCAAGCCAGUCAUUUGAAGAGGUUUUCUUUUCAUGCUGGAGGGCAGGCUAAGAUCAAUGAGUGGAAGAGAGAAAGGCUGUUUUAGCUCAAGUUAAAGGAACACCUUCUAGCCAUCAAAGCCGCCCAACAGAGGCAAGGGCCACCACACAUGAGAGAGCGCUCUGUCCUUAAAGGGAAUUCUCUGUUGAGUGGGAGGUGAACACCCUGGUUCUUCCAACUCAGGAAUUCUCGUGGCUGGGCUGGGUCAGUGAUGGCUUUGUCUCUUUAUGUCUAAAGUGCCCUAUGGCUGCUGAAGGUUACCUAACCAUUCUUUAAAAGGAGAAUGACCCUCCAUGGGAAUGGCCAGCCUGCCAACUGUGCAAUUGAAGAAGACCCGAUGGAUCAACCCCAUGUCUCCCUUGGGGAGAAAGUGCAUAAACCAGGGGUCUCUUUUUUUUUUUCAACAAACCAUUGAGCUGUUCUUGGAGUUCAUCUCUGGAGAGGUUAUACAUUAUUAGAAGUUUGAUUAUUAUUAUAGUUUGAUCAAUUUAUUUGUCUUAGAGAUCCAAUUUUUACUAAUUCCCUAGUUUUUUAUUUCAGCAUCUGAAUGUCUUUCUCCCUAGCACAGUGCAUACAAUCAGGGCCUUGGGUAUUUCCAGUGAUAACUUUCCUUGGAGAGGAUCUAAGAAAAGCCCAGAUUUCGGUAGCCAUCUCCCUCCAAAUAUGUCUCUUUCUGCUUUCUUAGUGCCCAUUAUUUCCCCCUCUCCUUUCUUCUGUCACUGCCAUCUCCUUCUUGGUCUUCCCAUUGUUCUUUAACUGGCCGUAAUGUGGAAUUGAUAUUUACAUUUUGAUACGGUUUUUUUCUUGGCCUGUGUACGGGAUUGCCUCAUUUCCUGCUCUGAAUUUUAAAAUUAGAUAUUAAAGCUGUCAUAUGGUUUCCUCACAAAAGUCAACAAAGUCCAAACAAAAAUAGUUUGCCGUUUUACUUUCAUCCAUUGAAAAAGGAAAUUGUGCCUCUUGCAGCCUAGGCAAAGGACAUUUAGUACUAUCGAUUCUUUCCACCCUCACGAUGACUUGCGGUUCUCUCUGUAGAAAAGGGAUGGCCUAAGAAAUACAACUAAAAAAACAAACAAAAACACCAAAAGAAAAAAAAAAGCCAUUUAAAGCCAGCCACUAGAGGGAGUCAGUUCAGUUCCGUAAAGGUAUGCUCAGUGCCCGCUGCCUGCAAGCUGUUGGGGACCCCAGGGAGGGCAAGGCAGCCUGUCCCCGCCCCCAGGGAACUAGAACAUGACAAGAAUUCUCCGCACUGUGCCUACCUGUCCCUUUACCUUACCUCUCUGGCCCAGAGUUCUUGGAGGGUUUUUUCUUUAUUUUCUUAUGUACUCAUCUACUUAUUCUCAAAGUAUUUAGCAUUCAACACUCUUUUUGCUUUAAAAAGAAUGGCCUUACAAAGGGACAGAAAAGAGAAGACACGAGCUUGGUGUAUUUUCAUCAAGUUAUGUGGCAGAGAAAUCCAGAUAUUACCAGGACCUGUCUAAACAAAUGUUGUGGGUUUUCUUUUCAUUCGGAUAGCCACUUUAUAGUUGGAAUAUCAAUUCUAAUGAGGAGGAAGACAUAAAUAUAAGUGGUAAAAAGAAACAUGACUUCCCUUAAAACAGGCUGGAUAAUCUAUAUCAGCCUUGUGGGUGGAGACUAGUAUUUGAUCCUUGCCAUAUAAAACAUUUUAAUAUGGUUUACAUGGGAAAAUAUCGAUGGCUUCCUCACAAAAUGUAUGGGUGACGUGAAGUUGAAGAGCCAAUGGCUUGGGUGACACGUGCUGGAUCCAAAAAGAUCAGGGAGACUAGAAUAAAACUUGGAUGUUAAAAAUUCACCAGGAAUCCACAUAAAGUACUAUAUUUGGGCUAAAAUGAAAAACUAAAUACAAGGUGGGAGAGAGGCAAGAAUUUCAGUUGACUAAGCUCAGUGUGAGUCAAAGUGGGAUGGAACCAUGCAAAAACAAAACCCACAGACAUGCAGGCUACGUGAGGAGAAAACAGUGGUGAGGAUCACAUCACAUUGUGUUUGCAUUUGCCGGAACCAUACUUUAAGAAGAAAACCGAUCAUCUAUAAUAACAUCAGUUUAUCAAUGCCCCGUCCUGAUGAAGUGUGCAGACUCUCAGAAACAGCAGGAAGGACUUCAUGAGAACCCUCAGGCUGGAGAAGGCACUAGGGCACAAGGAGAGCUCUCCUAGGACCAGGACCAAGAAGCUACAGGCAGGCACAGUUUAGCUCCUGCAGAGACCCAGCUUUUCACAAGUUGGAGCCUUCCAGAGAUAGAGGGACUGUGGUAGGUGGUGACCCACCCAUCACUGGAGGUGGAAGCAGAGGCCGUUUGCCAGGGAUGCUGGAGAGGGGAUUCAAGCAUCUGGCUGGGCAACGUGAUGCUCAGGGCCGUCUCCACUCAGGGCUUAGGGGAGUCUGUGAGUAGAAGAGCUUUAGGUGAUUUGUUUGGUGGGGGAAGGCAAGUACACAGCUAUGCACUUUCCGUUUCUGACUUUUGCCACCCUGUCAGCCAUGGGGAGCCCACUGUGGGACUGAAACCCUGAGCUGAAUGCGGCCUCAUGUCUCAGAGAAACACUGGCAAGUUGGUCAGAGCCGCCGUCUGCAUCGAGGCGUAGCUGAGCGGCAGGAUGGGGGGCUGCCUGCCCAGGGUCUCUCACCGUGGUGUAAGCAGAGCCAUGGCUUGCCUAGGACCCUAUAGAUACCAUCACUCUUUCUCAGCUCGACUGGAGUUUCUGCACCUUUGCAGGGGCAAAGUAACUCCCUGCACCCUGAACCACCCCCCAUUCCUGUUCAUUUCAGCAGAUAAUGAUGGAGGGGGGGGGUGUCCAUCGUGCUGAGGGUGUGACCGCAAGAGGGUGAAAACUUCCAGCCAACUUUCUCAGUCCUUUCUCUUGCGAGAGGGAAGCCACCUGCUAUACAAACUAAUACCCCCUGCCUUGACCCCUUCCCCACGACUCAGUUGACAGAAGGAUAUACUUUGUUAUAACUUAUUAUUUUGUUCUCUGUAAAUACAAGAUGUUUAUAGGAAAUAUGUAUUCUGAACUCUAUCUGCAGAAUGAGUCACUACACCAAAAUAGUUCUAUUAUUUAGAAUGUGUUAAUUUUAAAGGGACCUGAUAGGUAUUUAUUUACAUAUGCGAUCCACAUUUGUGUGAAAGCAUGUGAUCAUACUAACCCAGCCUCCUGGAAUGUCGCUGUACGAUGAUUGAUGUCUUUUUCUCAGUCCAUAGUUACAAUUGUUUAGUAUGCUAAUCAGUCCAGUUCCCUGAGGUUUAAGAUCAAAUAUAAAUUACUCUGCUUUUCGACUCAUUCAGGUAGCAUUGUACCUGAACCUGAUUGCUACUUUUUCAUCUUAAAUAUUAUAUUUCCUCAUCUAAUCUGCCUUCCCCUCAUCCACAGACAUUUGGAGAAGGAAAUGGGAGGGUGUCUGUUAUCCCUUUCUCUUUGCUUUGUCCCCGUUGUUAGACUGGCAGCGUCAGUUGCUCGGUGGGCUUGGUUAGAGCCGUGGGUGAGGCAGGUGGCUGGCGGGGACAGGGAGAGGCUGAGAGGGAAGUGGUGGCAUUUACUGCUCUGACACUUCCACUGUCCCUGCUGGGGAUGCUGGGGCCAAGGCCUGUGGGGCCUGUGAACUGCACAGCCAGGAGCAAGGAACCCACUAAAUACUCCGUCACCUCCAUGUCCCCUCUACAGUGUUAAAUUAUUACAUAAGCAGGUGAAAGGUAGAAGGCGAAUUAUGUGAGUAAAUAUGGUCUGUUUUCUCUUCAGCAAAAAUGACUAUUUUUGUGUGUGACUAAUUUAUUUUUAUUAUUGUAAAGAUACAAUAAACCGGUUGAAAUAUCUGCUUUGUUGACAAGCGUGUGCUUUCUCUGGCCUUAUUCGCGUUCUGUUCUCCUGCAAAUAGCGCCCUCUAAAAAGAAGAGUCAGACAAUAAACUGGUUGAAAUAUC